GACUUCCGUUUCGGUCCAGCCGGGCUGCGGCCAUUGUUUGUGUGGACUGAGUGUUUUGGCCAUCCCGGUCCACUCUCACAGGCUCCGUUAAGUGACAUGAACUCUCAGGAGGACUGAGCCAGAAGCGGACAGGGCAAGACGAGCUGUGCUUGAAGGAAGAGGGGCAGAAAAUCGAGGGUCAGGGACUGAGAAGCUACUCCGGUUUAGAAACCCCAGAGACACCCGUGUAGAUGGGUACAUCACGGCUUCUCUCCCACGUUAAGACUUAAUAAAGGAACCUACCUUUGAUCAGCAAGGAAGGACUGGGGUGGCAAAGGCUCAUGCCCCCAUUUUACAGAAAGCCUGAUCUUUGACCAGAUGGCAGUAACAUUUGAAGAUGUGACUAUUAUUUUUACAUGGGAGGAGUGGAAAUUCCUGGAUUCUUCUCAAAAAAGACUCUACAGGGAGGUCAUGUGGGAGAACUACACAAAUGUCAUGUCAGUAGAAAACUGGAAUGAGAGCUACAAAUCCCAAGAAGAAAAAUUCAGAUACUUAGAAUAUGAAAAUUUUUCCUACUGGCAAGGCUGGUGGAAUGCUGGCGCCCAGAUGUAUGAGAAUCAGAACUAUGGGGAAACUGUUCAAGGGACAGAUUCCAAAGACCUCACACAGCAAGAUCGUUCCCAGUGUCAGGAAUGGUUAAUACUCUCCACACAAGUACCAGGGUAUGGGAACUAUGAACUGACUUUUGAAAGCAAAAGUCUCAGGAACUUAAAAUAUAAAAAUUUUAUGCCUUGGCAGUCCUUAGAAACAAAAACCACUCAAGACUAUGGUAGAGAAAUCUACAUGAGUGGUUCACAUGGUUUUCAAGGGGGCAGAUACCGUCUUGGCAUAUCCAGGAAAAACCUCUCCAUGGAAAAAGAACAGAAGCUCAUAGUUCAGCAUUCUUAUAUCCCAGUGGAGGAAGCCCUUCCACAGUAUGUUGGGGUGAUAUGUCAAGAAGACCUACUGAGAGAUUCAAUGGAAGAAAAGUACUGUGGAUGUAAUAAAUGUAAAGGAAUUUAUUAUUGGAACUCACGGUGUGUUUUCCACAAGAGAAAUCAACCUGGAGAAAACCUCUGUCAAUGCUCCAUCUGUAAAGCAUGCUUCUCUCAGAGAUCAGACUUGUAUAGACAUCCAAGAAACCACAUAGGUAAGAAGCUGUACGGAUGUGAUGAAGUUGACGGUAACUUUCAUCAGAGCUCCGGAGUUCACUUUCAUCAGAGAGUUCACAUAGGGGAGGUACCUUAUAGCUGUAAUGCAUGUGGUAAGAGCUUCAGCCAGAUCUCUAGUCUUCACAAUCAUCAAAGAGUCCACACAGAAGAGAAAUUCUAUAAAAUUGAGUGUGAUAAAGACCUCAGUAGAAAUUCAUUACUUCACAUUCACCAGAGACUUCACAUAGGAGAGAAGCCUUUUAAAUGUAAUCAGUGUGGUAAGAGUUUUAAUCGGAGUUCAGUACUUCAUGUUCAUCAGAGAGUCCACACAGGAGAAAAACCAUAUAAGUGUGAUGAGUGUGGUAAGGGUUUCAGCCAGAGCUCAAAUCUUCGAAUUCAUCAGUUAGUACACACAGGAGAGAAGUCUUAUAAAUGUGAAGACUGUGGUAAAGGCUUUACCCAGCGCUCAAAUCUUCAAAUUCAUCAGAGAGUGCAUACAGGAGAGAAACCUUAUAAAUGUGAUGACUGUGGAAAGGACUUUAGUCACAGCUCAGAUCUUCGCAUUCAUCAGAGAGUCCAUACAGGGGAGAAACCCUAUACUUGUCCUGAAUGUGGGAAGGGCUUCAGUAAGAGUUCAAAGCUUCACACUCAUCAAAGAGUACAUACUGGAGAGAAACCCUACAAAUGUGAAGAGUGUGGCAAGGGAUUCAGUCAGCGUUCACAUCUUCUCAUUCAUCAGAGAGUCCAUACAGGAGAAAAGCCCUAUAAAUGUCAUGAUUGUGGAAAGGGUUUUAGUCACAGUUCUAAUCUUCACAUUCAUCAGAGGGUCCAUACAGGAGAGAAGCCUUAUCAAUGUGCUAAGUGUGGUAAAGGUUUCAGUCAUAGCUCAGCUCUUCGAAUUCAUCAAAGAGUCCAUGCAGGAGAGAAACCUUACAAAUGCCGUGAAUAUUAUAAGGGAUUUGAUCAUAAUUCACAUCUUCACAAUAAUCAUAGAAGAGGAAACUUAUAAAUAUUGUUCAUUUAGUUAACAGCUUUAAUCAAAGUUUACCUAACCUUUAAACCCUAUAAAUCCUGCUGUUAAGGAAAUCUUAUAAAUAACACAAGUAAUCCCAAGCAACAUUUAUAGUUUCCCCUAUCUCCCACUAAGAAUUAUUUGCUUCAAAAGGAGAUCUUUAGAAAAAACCCUAUAUAUUUAAAAUUAUAGUGUAUUUUUCUUUACCUACUAUAAAUAUAAUACAGUCAUAAAUAUAUUAAACAUUUAAGGAGAAAACUCUUCAUUCUAUUUCAUUCUAGUCUUUUUUUCUGUGCAUUUUAAUGUGCAUGAAAUUGUGUGUUCAAUUUUGUAUUUUCACUGUCUUCAAAAUAUUUACUUAAAUUUUGGUUUGAAUUGAAACUGGUUGGCCAACUGUUAAACGACAUCUCUUAACUCCCCUAAAAACUCCCUAGGAAGUAACAGAAAAGAUGGAAACACAUAGAACUUAAAACUCAGUUUUGGCCGGUAGAAUUCAAUUGUUUAUGGACAAAAGCCACCUAAUAAAAGAUAGGAAAGCAUUGUAUGACAUUGUGUCUGAGACAGUGUAUCUGAGUUGUUAUCUCUGUCAACCAGAAAACCCAGGGACCAUCCUUCUGUUGCAGGGGUGCUUCACUUUGAGGUGACUACAGUGCACUCAUCCCUUCCCUUUCCGGUUUUCCACGCUUAAUAAUAGGUUCAGAUACCAAACAACAAGAAGUACAGAAUUUUCUCUAAGGUGUGAAGGGUAUGGACAAAAGUGCUAGAAAUGGAAGAUACUCCAUUGGUUCGGAAUUAGAGAUCCAAGCAGUAGAAUUUUAUUUAAUCUCAGUAGAACAGAGUGGUAAUAGAGAAAUAUCUGCAAGGACAGCAUUGAACUCAGAACUCUGUGCAACGAUGAACCCUGAAGCUAAUUAUGUAAAAAGAGAGUUUGGCCAUUAUCUCAGAAUAGAGUUAGUCGGAAUACACAGUCUUAAUUAUUGAUACACAAAUAUGCUGAAGUAAUACCAAGAGAAAAAAAAGUGGACAUGUUUAGGAAAAUUAGAGGGAAUUGCAAUACUGAAGAAAAGAAUAUCAUCCUAAAGACCUGGAAACUUAUUGCCCUGAAAAUUAGCUGCUGCAGGCUUCAGAGGAAAUUUCCAGAAAUGUUGGUGUCCUUAGUGGCAUAACAGAGAAUCUGAACUCAGUAAAGAUAGAGUAGAAAUAUACAAGUAGAGAAGAGUAUCUAAAGUGAAAAGAGAAAUAGAUACAACAAAGAAGGACUUCAGGGAGCUCUGAAAUACUGUAUCAAAAUAAAUGCAAUAAAAAGUAACACUGAAGAAUAUAAAAUAAUUGAUAGUUAAUAGAUAAACUUGAUCUGAUCUUAAAUGUAUCUGAAAAGGAUAAUGAGAUGGAAACUAAGAAAGAACAGAUAUGAAUAUCAGAGGAUGGAGGUCCAGUGUGAGAAUUAAAGGUGUCUCUAAGGAAGGUGAAAGAACAUUUGGCAUAGAAUCAAUGAUCAAAGACAUUAAGAAACUUUCUCUGAGUUAAAAGUAUAUGGUCACUAAGUUUUAGGCAAAACCAGUAUUAAAGCAACCUUAGAAACAGGUUAGAAAGAAGCAAUUAAAAGCAUGCAGAAAGAAAAAUUCUGGUUAUCUGCAAAACCAGAAAGGGAGGGUGGAUACAGAGCUCUGCAACAGUAACUCAGAAGGCAAUGGAGCAGCACGUUCAGAAUUUUGAGAUUUGAAAAGUUUAUUAUCACCAGUUUUAUAACAAAAGUGUCUUUCAUAUGUGCAGGAAACAAAUAUUUUUGAUAAGCAAGAAAACAGUGUAGCGUAUAUGUGCCUUAAAGAGAGUUUGUGAAUGUGGAAAUCAUGGUAUAAAAGGACUAGUGAUAAGCACUGAAAUCAAUUAGAUAUGCAGUUGUCUGGAUAGUUUCCAAAACUUCAAAAAAUUAAAUGUGCAAUAAAAAUAUACAAAUGCUGAGUGUAAAGUGUACAAAUGCUGAGUCUGGGUAGGAGAGUAAGGUUGUCAGGACACCCAGUUAAGUUUGAAUUUCAUAUAAGCAAAGAAUAAUUGUUUUAGUAUAAGGGUGUCCCAAAUAUUGCAUGGGACUUACACUAAAAUUUCAUACAUUUGAAAUUCAAAUUUAACUGGUCAUUUCUGUUUUUAGUUGCUACAUCCGGCAACUGGAGAGAGACCAUAAGUGCCACAUUUCUGAUCUUAAAUAGCAGGGACUCAUAAUAACAUUUUCUUUUUGAAUGACAAUUUAAGAAAGGCCUUUUUUUUUUUUUUUUACAAACCUAAAAUUACAACUUAAUAAAACUAAAAAAAGUGCAUAUACCUUUCAAAAUGGGAGAAGAUAAAAGCAAAAAUUAUUCAGUCUCUGUAGCAAUGACUACCAAAAAAAUCCCCAAGAAGUUGGCCUAAAAUAUUAAAAUAAACGGAUCAAGAUGAUUAAAGCCAAAUGUAUCAAAACACGUUCAAUGCUUCAUUUUAAAAUGUUGAAAACACUGGGUUAAAAAUUUCUAAUUAUGUGCUAUAACAGAUGAAAAUGUGAUAUUGCUUAAAUGUGAGACCAGGUGAAGGUUUAUUAGACAAACAUAAAGGAGUACCUACAAUAUGUUUUUAAAGGUGAAAAGUGCACUAAUUUAAACUCAUUAAGUUGGGCAAAAAUACAAAAUCAUUAGUUUUCUAAAUUCUUGGAAUAUUCAGGAAAUGUAAUUGUCAAAAAAUCUGGUUUUUAAUUUACAAAAAUGCAGAAUGAAAAUAAUAAAAAACGGGGAAAUAUAAAAGAG